GGGUUUUCGGCGGGGCCAACCCACGGUGGGGGGAGCGCGGCCAUGGCGCUCCUGCUUUCGGUGCUGCGUGUACUGCUGGGCGGCUUCUUCGCGCUCGUGGGGUUGGCCAAGCUCUCGGAGGAGAUCUCGGCUCCAGUUUCGGAGCGGAUGAAUGCCCUGUUCGUGCAGUUUGCUGAGGUGUUCCCGCUGAAGGUAUUUGGCUACCAGCCAGAUCCCCUGAACUACCAAAUAGCUGUGGGCUUUCUGGAACUGCUGGCUGGGUUGCUGCUGGUCAUGGGCCCACCGAUGCUGCAAGAGAUCAGUAACUUGUUCUUGAUUCUGCUCAUGAUGGGGGCUAUCUUCACCUUGGCAGCUCUGAAAGAGUCACUAAGCACCUGUAUCCCAGCCAUUGUCUGCCUGGGGUUCCUGCUGCUGCUGAAUGUCGGCCAGCUCUUAGCCCAGACUAAGAAGGUGGUCAGACCCACUAGGAAGAAGACUCUAAGUACAUUCAAGGAAUCCUGGAAGUAGAGCAUCUCUGUCUCUUUAUGCCAUGCAGCUGUCACAGCAGGAACAUGGUAGAACACAGAGUCUAUCAUCUUGUUACCAGUAUAAUAUCCAGGGUCAGCCAGUGUUGAAAGAGACAUUUUGUCUACCUGGCACUGCUUUCUCUUUUUAGCUUUACUACUCUUUUGUGAGGAGUACAUGUUAUGCAUAUUAACAUUCCUCAUGUCAUAUGAAAAUACAAAAUAAGCAGAAAAGAAAUUUAAAUCAACCAAAAUUCUGAUGCCCCAAAUAACCACUUUUAAUGCCUUGGUGUAAGUAUACCUCUGAACUUUUUUCUGUGCCUUUAAACAGAUAUAUAUUUUUUUUAAAUGAAAAUAAAACCAUAUAUCCUAUUUUAUUUCCUCCUUUUAAAACCUUAUAAACUAUAACACUGUUUCAUGUCUCUUUUGCCUCAUUGCUGUUAAUGGCUGCAUAGUAUUCCAUUGCAAGGAUGUACUAUAAUGUAUUUAAUCCCCCAUGAGGAACAUUUGGGUUAUUCUCAAUUUUUUGCUCUCGUAAGCCUCACAGUAAAUCACUUUUGCAUACUUA